CCAGCCCCCAGCAUCAUUUUCUUCAGAGAACAUUCGAGGAUUCUUCAUGAUGGCUGGGCUUUUUUUUUUUUUUUUUUUUUUGAGACGGAGUUUCACUCUUGUUGCCCAGGCUGGAGUGCAAUGGCACAAUCUUGGCUCACCACAACUUCUGCCCCCUGAGUUCAAGCAGUUCUGCCUCAGCCUCCCGAGUAGCUAGGAUUAUAGGCAUGCACAAUCACACCUGGCUAAUUUUGUAUUUUUAGUAGAGACGAGGUUUCUCCAUGUUGAUCAAGCUAGUCAGGAACGCUCGACCUCAGGUGAUCCGCCCGCCUUGGCCUCCCAAAGUGCUGGGAUUACAGGCGUGGGCCACCACUCCCGGCGAUGCCUGGGCUUUCAUUGGGUAUUAAGUCUACAAACAGCACCUUCAAUUUAAACUGUCAAUUACAGUUCUUAAGAUUUAGGAAGUGAUGGAGCUUGGAAAGUUACGAGAUUACAAAAUCCGUGAAAGUCCAUUAGAAAAACCACAAGAUGGAAAAAAGUAUAAACCAGGCCACAAAGAAGCUUCAGAGGUCCCUGCUGUCCCAGGGACAGAUACCUGCAGUGUCCAGCAUCUCAGUGAACAUGACCUGCUUUCAAAGGCAGGGGCUUAAAGCGAGGGUGGCAUGGGACCGGUGGAGGCAAAGUGUUGGGGUGAUCAGACCCAACACCUGGUCACUGGGGCUAUGAAGUCUGGCAGAGUCAAAGGAAUGAGACAAGACAAGAGUACAUAGGGUGGGUCUCAGGGGCCAACGCCAGUAUGGAGGCUGCAAAGGCCCUGAGCUCUAGGAGCCCACACUAUUUAUUGGUAAUCAAACAAAGAAGCAGGUGGAGAGGACGUGCGGAUGUGGGGGCAGACAGGUGAGGAUGUGGGGGUAGAAAGCGGUGCAUCAAGCGUAGCUGUGAUGGCUUAGCAUAUGCUCUGCUACUUGAGAUAAGGGAGAAUAGGUUCUUCUAAUUCAAGAUACAAUCAAUUUAUGAUCUUGGGAGAACAAAGUGCAAGGGGCCAGUGAGUCUGGACACACUCCAAAGGCUACAGAGGGUUUUAUGCCCUGAGCCCUGGGUUCUCUCCAAGCCACAAGGGGUUUCAUACCCUGGGUUUAGAUUGUACUGCGGCAGGGCAGCCUUCCACCCUUUGGCACAGAGUUUGGUGUUCCAAAGGUCAUGAGGGGUUUUAGACCCUGGACCCAGGACAUGUUCCAAGACUCUUUUACAUUAUGUCAGAAAAACGAGCCCUGCCUCAGCUCUUCUGCCAACAUGUCUCCCUUUUUUGUCCUGCAAAACCGCCACAGCUAUCAUUGCUUGUUCUUGGCAGCGGCUUUCUCUCCAGAAGCGGCUUCCGCAUCUGUAGAUUAAAAGGAGACAGCACAAGCACAUAAUUAUUAGAACAAAAUUUACAAGUGUAGAGUUUCCAGUGGUCUUAAUCCAUUUAAGAGAAUUGAUUGCAGACAACCCAUUGGCUGCCUCGCUGAAAAUAUCAGUUCCAGGGAGCAGGGUUAAGUGAGCCUGAGAGGCUUCAAAAACCUGCUCUUUUACUUUUACAAUAUCAAGGGUGAGAUUUUCCUCUCUGCCCACUAGAUGGCAUUUAAUUUCCCAUUGGUGUUCUGUUUCAUUCUAACUAUGAGGAGUAACGCAAAAAUCGGAUGUAUUCCAGUCACAUUGCAUUUGAAUUCUAGUUUCUAAACUUAUGAUGCAAUCCCCCAUCCAAAUUACUGUCUGAGGGAGAUCAUUAAUUUGACUAACUAUAUUUUGAUCUGUUUGGGCCUGAGAGCUCCAUAAUUUCAUAGAAUUCUUUUUCCAUUUAUCAACAAAUUUGACAGUUUGCACAGAUGAGUGUAAAGCCACACUAGCUACUGCAGCAGUGGUGGUAACUGCAGUGAGGCCAAUUAUAGCAAAUAUAAGAGCAACUAUAAAUCUUUUUGAACGGGAUAAGAGUUUUGUAAGGAUCUCAGUUAUAAUGUGAAUGGACGGUGAUGCCUCCCAUGGUCUAUUUAGAGACACAGGGAUCCAAACUCCUUCUCUGGCUCUAAUUAACAAGAUAGUUUGAUUUUUAUCAAGAUGUCGUUAAUGCAAGUAAACAAGUGACAUUCCUGGCAGGUGAUAAAACGGGUAUUUAUGUAAAGAGUAAUAUUUCCGGCCUGGCGGGGUGGCUCACACCUGUAAUCCCAGCACUUUGGGAGGCUGCGGCGGGCGGAUCAUGAGGCCAGAAGAUCAAGACCAUCCUGGCUAACACGGUGAAACUCCGUCUCUACUAAAAAAAAUAAAUAAAUAAAAAGCCACAAAAAAUUAGCCGGGCAUGGUGGUGGGCGCCUGUAGUCCCAGCUACUCGGGAGGCUGAGGCAGGAGAAAGGCAUGAACCAGGGAGGCAGAGCGUGCAGUGGGCCUAGAUCACACCACUGCACUCCAGCCUGGGGGACAGAGCGAGACUCCGGUCUCAAAAAAAAAAAAAGAAGAGUAAUAUUUCCUACUGCUAACGUAAAAGGUGGUCGGACACAAUUUUGAUUCCAAAAGGUCCUGUUAGAAAGAAAAGAGAGAACAUAUUUAUAUUUACCUCCCUCCCCUUUAUACUUAUUAUAUUUACCCUCCCAAAUUGUGAUUGAACUUUGAGCCAUAGCUAAUUUCCAUAAUCCUGAAUGUUCCUGUCCUAUGGCAGGAGAUAUCAUUUUUGGAAUAGGGGUGAUAAUGCCACCAGGGCUCCAUAUAAUAGGAACAUCAGCUUCCGUCUGAAUGUACCGUGUAUGGUUCUCUUUCCAAUGAGUCCAUCAGCUUAUUUUAUAAGAAGGCCCUUCAGUGCAAUUUUUCUUAAAAAUCCCCUUAGGGGACCAGUCAAUGACGAUUCCAUAGGAAUUAUUUUGUAGCACCCCAGCCUUACUUGCUACACAAUUUCCCCAAUGCCAAGCGUCCACACCUUCAAACCAAACUCUAUUUUGUUUACAUUCGAGUUUGUCUGGUCAGAACUGCUGAGUUUCAGGGCUGGAAUGGUUAUAUUUUAAACUUUGCCCUGAAAUCAUAUAUAAAGUAGCCUGUGAUUUAUUUUUUCCAGGGAUUACUGCCAACCAUACUUGUGUGCCAAUUUGUAAGCAUCCAGCAGCAGGUCCUAGGCAUAUUGGAGGAUAUUUAUAUCCUAUUGAUAUAUUCAUUUUCAUCCCUUCCUCAUUAGGAUGCAUCGGCACUCUGUUAUCUAUGGGCUCAGGCAUCGAGGUUCUGUCAUUGUUGUACACCUCAAUAAUAGGGUCCAUCCAACUCACAGACCUAAUUAAAGGAGGAAAUGGGACAUAAGUCCAAUAAGUAAAAUUUUGAGUUGCUUUUACAGUAGGGAGGCUUACCGCCACAGUAAGUACCACCAUCAUAGCCACCAUUAGGUUACUAGUUGUUUUUGAUUUGUUCUGUGCUCUCAGAUUGUCCUCUGCAUCUGUGCCAGUUUCCUGAUUUGUCCCCAUGUUGGAGGGUCUGCCUGGAGAGGCUCCUGAGCGCUAGGUCCGCACUGUGGUGACUGAACCCAGAAGUCGGGGAGCAGUUGUCCUCCGCUGCACAGAGGCUACUCUGGAGCUCUGUGACGGCGCCCAGCGUGACCCACUCCUGGGCCAGGAUACGGACCGUCGUGCCCAUAUCUCCUGGCUGGUCGCCCUAUCCUCCCGACUCUGCUUAAAACCACGUGGUUCGAUGGCUGCCGCGGCUACGCUGAGGCUCUCCGCUCAGGGCACAGUGACUUUUGAAGAUGUGGCUGUGAACUUUACCUGGGAGGAAUGGAAUCUCCUUAGUGAGGCUCAGAGAUGCCUGUACCGUGAUGUGACGCUGGAGAACCUGGCACUUAUAUCCUCCCUGGGUUGUUGGUGUGGAGUGGAAGAUGAGGCGGCACCUUCUAAGCAGAGUAUUUAUAUACAAAGAGAGACUCAGGUCAGGACUCCUAUGGCAGGUGUGUCUCCCAAGAAGGCCCACCCCUGUGAGAUGUGUGGCCCGAUCUUGGGAGACAUUUUGCAUGUGGCAGAUCAUCAGGGAACACAUCACAAGCAGAAACUGCACAGGUGUGAGGCCUGGGGGAAUAAAUUGUAUGACAGUGGAAACUUUCAUCAGCACCAGAAUGAGCACAUUGGAGAGAAACCCUACAGAGGGAGUGUUGAGGAGGCGUUGUUUGCAAAGAGGUGUAAGUUGCAUGUGUCAGGGGAGUCAUCUGUCUUCAGUGAGAGUGGGAAGGACUUUUUGCCCAGGUCAGGAUUACUCCAGCAGGAGGCCAGUCACACUGGGGAGAAGUCAAACAGCAAAACUGAGUGUGUGUCUCCCAUUCAGUGUGGGGGAGCUCACUACAGCUGUGGAGAAUCCAUGAAACAUUUUAGCACCAAACAUAUACUCAGUCAGCACCAGAGACUGCUCACUAGAGAAGAGUGUUAUGUGUGCUGUGAAUGUGGGAAGUCCUUUAGCAAAUAUGCUAGCUUGAGUAAUCAUCAGAGAGUUCACACUGAAAAAAAACAUGAAUGUGGAGAAUGUGGGAAAUCCUUUAGCAAAUAUGUUAGCUUCAGUAAUCAUCAGAGAGUUCACACUGAAAAAAAACAUGAAUGUGGAGAAUGUGGGAAAUCCUUUAGCAAAUAUGUUAGCUUCAGUAAUCAUCAGAGAGUUCACACUGGGAAAAGACCUUAUGAAUGUGGAGAAUGUGGGAAAUCGUUUAGCAAAUAUGCUAGCUUCAGUAAUCAUCAGAGAGUUCACACUGAAAAAAAACAUUAUGAAUGUGGAGAAUGUGGGAAAUCCUUUAGCAAAUAUGUUAGCUUCAGUAAUCAUCAGAGAGUUCACACUGGGAAAAGACCUUAUGAAUGUGGAGAAUGUGGGAAAUCGUUUAGCAAAUAUGCUAGCUUCAGUAAUCAUCAGAGAGUUCACACUGACAAAAAACAUUAUGAAUGUGGAGAAUGUGGGAAAUCCUUUAGUCAAAAGAGCAGCCUCAUUCAACAUCAGCGAUUUCACACUGGAGAAAAACCUUAUGGGUGUGAAGAAUGUGGGAAAUCUUUUAGUUCAGAAGGACAUCUUAGGAGCCAUCAACGAGUUCACGCCGGAGAAAGACCUUUCAAGUGUGGAGAAUGUGUGAAAUCUUUCAGUCAUAAGCGCAGCCUUGUUCACCAUCAGCGAGUUCACAGUGGAGAAAGACCUUAUCAGUGUGGAGAAUGUGGGAAAUCUUUCAGUCAAAAGGGCAACCUCGUUCUACACCAGCGAGUUCACACUGGAGCAAGACCUUAUGAGUGUGGAGAAUGUGGGAAAUCAUUUAGUUCAAAAGGACAUCUUAGGAACCAUCAGCAAAUUCACACUGGGGACAGACUUUAUGAGUGUGGAGAGUGUGGGAAAUCUUUUAGUCAUAAAGGCACCCUCAUUCUACAUCAGCGAGUUCACCCUAGAGAAAGAUCUUAUGGGUGUGGAGAAUGUGGGAAAUCUUUUAGUUCAAUCGGGCACCUUAGGAGCCAUCAGCGCGUUCAUACUGGAGAGAGGCCUUAUGAGUGUGGAGAAUGUGGGAAAUCUUUUAGUCAUAAGCGCAGCCUUGUUCACCAUCAGCGCAUGCACACUGGAGAAAGACCUUACAAGUGUGGAGACUGUGGGAAAUCUUUUAAUGAAAAAGGACACCUUAGGAAUCAUCAGCGAGUUCACACUACAGAAAGACCUUUUAAGUGUGGGGAAUGUGGGAAAUGUUUUAGUCACAAGGGUAACCUCAUUCUACACCAGCAUGGCCAUACUGGAGAAAGACCUUAUGUAUGUAGGGAAUGUGGAAAAUUAUUUAAGAAGAAGUCUCACCUCCUUGUACACCAGAGAAUUCACAAUGGAGAAAAGCCAUAUGCUUGUGAAGCUUGUCAGAAAUUUUUUAGAAACAAGUACCAACUCAUUGCACAUCAGAGAGUUCACACUGGAGAAAGGCCUUAUGAAUGCAAUGAUUGUGGAAAAUCAUUUACCCACAGCUCUACAUUCUGUGUUCAUAAGCGAAUUCACACUGGAGAAAAGCCUUAUGAGUGCAGUGAAUGUGGAAAAUCUUUCGCUGAAAGCUCCAGUUUCACAAAACACAAAAGAGUUCACACUGGAGAAAAGCCUUAUGAGUGCAGUGAAUGUGGAAAAUCUUUUGCUGAAAGCUCCAGUCUCACUAAACACAAGAGAGUUCACACUGGAGAAAAGCCUUAUAAAUGUGAGAAAUGUGGGAAAUUAUUUAACAAGAAGUCUCACCUCCUUGUACACCAGAGUUCACACUGGAGAAAAGCCAUAUGAGUGUGAGGAUUGUCAGAAAGUUUUUAGCAAGAAGGACCACCUCAUUGCACACCAGAGAGUUCACACUGGAGAAAGGCCAUAUGAAUGCAGUGAUUGUGGGAAGUCAUCUACCCACAGCUCUGCAUUCUGUGUUCAUAAGAGAGUUCACACUGGUCACACCACCUUAUGAGUGCAGUGAAUGUGGGAAAUCCUUUGCUGAAACUUUCAGUCUCAUUAAACACAGGAGAGUUCACACUGGAGUAAGGUCUUGUGAUUGCAGCAAAUGUGGGAAAAAAGUUACCUGAAGGUCUUUUCUCCUUGAAUAUCAGAGAGUUCACACUAGACAAAUAAAAUACAUUUGGGCAAUUUUGUAGCCACACCUCUUUGCUCCUUCAAGAUCAGAGUUAACACUGGAUCAGGGCCUUACCAGUGUGACAUGUGAGAUAUUUAUGUAGAAAUCUAGCUUCAUAACACACAGGAGACUUCCCACUGCAGAAAUGCCUUUUGAAUGUAAUGAAUGCAAGAAAGCCUUCAGCCUUUUUAUUGGAGCCUCAAACAUUGACAUGAGAAAAACACCAUAGAUGUAUAUGGAAUGUUAUUUCUUUUUCAAUGUAACCCUUUGAGAGUGCCACCUACCUAGAUUGAAUGUCAUUUAUUGAGCAUCUGCAAAAGUUCCAAGUGUGUGGCAGCUACAGUGCAUUUUUCACUAUACCCAGGUACCUUGCUAGAUUUUUUUUGAGACAGGUUGUCACUGUGUCGCUCAGGAUGGCGUGCAGUGGUGUGUUCACAUUUCACUGCACCCUUGAUCUGGGCUUAAGUGAUUCUGUUGCCUCGGCCUCCUGAGUAGCUGAAACCACAGGCAUGCACUACCAUGCUCCACUAAUUUUUUUAAGUUUUGGAGAGACAGGGUCUCACCAUGUUGCCCAGGCUGGUCUUAAACUCCUGGCUCAAGCGAUCCUUCCACCUUGGCCUCCAAACAUGCUGGGAUUACAGGUGUGAGUUACUGUGCCUGGCCUUUUUUUUUUUUUUUUUUAACUUUUAAUUUCUGAUCGAGUCACAGAAGGAUUUGUUGAGUAGCUUCAGCACUUCUUCCUUUGUCAUUUUUUUCUGUCUGAUAAGUCAUGCCAUGGACGUUACCCAUUUUUAUCCCAGAGGCCUCUUACGUUGACUUGAAAAGACGGACUAUGUCUUUCAGAGAUCUUGUGGGUAUCACAUCAAUCUUGACAAAUUUUCUACCCUCCAAGUCAUGAUCCUAAGAACAGCUUGCCUCCCAUUUCUCCGGUUUGUGCUAUUAUGAAGGCCUUAUUGUUUCAGCCUUCUUCAAUCUUGAGGGUUGUUGUCACUGUAUGGGUGGUUCAGAAAUAAGUAGGUCCUGUUACUAUGAAGGGGGUCACAGCUUUUGUUGGCAUAGCUAAACUUUGUGGCUCAUGGAACAGUAUGAAUGCAGAAUGUAGCUUUCUCCACUUGUGGACUGCUUUGCAUAGCUGCCAGAGGCCUCCAGAGAAGACCUUCAGGGCUUUGUGGUCUUUAUCUGUAGCACGGAUACUAAAAUUUGUGGGUUCAUAGGUCAGCUGGAUACAGGGCAUUUUUUGUGACAAUUUCUGGCAUUUUUUGAACAAGACAAAAUUCUUUUACGAGGUAUAUUGCAUUGUACUUGGUACGGCUGAGGGAAGUCUGUUGCCCAGCUCUUGCAAUGCAGACACAUGCCCUGAUAUCCAGAAUUCUGUAGGAUAACAUCACAGAUUGUAAUGCUAUCAGGUGAAAUUAUAAUUUUAUAGAAUUACUUUAUUUAUAGGCAGUGGAGGAGACAGAAUAAUGUAACUGCAACUCAUGUCUUUUUUUUCUUUUUUUUUCUUUUUUUUUGAGGCAGAGCCUCACCCUGUUGCCCAGGCUGGAGUGCAGUGGCAUAAUCUUGGCUCACGGCAACCUCUGCCUCCCAGGUUCAAACGAUUCUCCUGCCUCAGCCUCCUGAGUAGCUGGGACUACAGGCACAUGCCACCACACCCAGCUAAUUUUUGUAUUUUUAGUAGAGAUGGGGUUUCACCAUGUUGGCCAGGCUGGUCUCGAACUCCUGACCUUGUGAUCUGCUGGCCUCAGCCUCCCAAAGUCCUGGGAUUACAGGUGAGCCACCACGUGCAGCGUAAUGCAUGUCUUUUAAAAGGGCAUCCACAAUGAUCCAGUCACUACGUAUAUGAUGAAUAUGCAGAUACAGGAAUUAUCAGGACUUCCAUAAUGAUGAAUAUUGUAUUGUUGAGGCCAUUGUCAGAGGAAAUAAUCUAAAGGUUUUGUGAAUUCCUGUACUCAUUCUGGGCUGUUCUCCUCAAGGUCAUUCCUGCAUUAACAGGAGGAAGAUGAUAGGGAGAAGGGAGAUCUCAGUUCAGUGAUGUGGCCUUUGUGACCAGCCAGCCACUUAAUCAGGUGGAAAUGGCCUUAGUGCCACAUCAAUAUUUGCUACCGUGGAGGCUAGUUUUCCCACUUAGGGCAUGAGAAGAAUUGGUGUAGUCAGUAUAGAGUUGCCAAACCUGUUUUCCAAAAAUAAUGGUAAAUCUAUAUUUUUCUUUUGAACUGCAUUUUUUUAAUUAUUAUUAUUAUUUAUUUUGAGACGGAGUCUUGCUCUGUUGCCCAGGCUGGAUGGAGUGCAGUGGCACGAUCUCGGCUCACUGCAAGCUCUGCCUCCUGGGUUCACACCAUUCUUCUGCCUCAGCCUCCCAAGUAGCUGGGACUACAGGUGCCCGCCACCAUACCCAGCUAAUUUUUUGUAUCUUUACUAGAGAUGGGGUUUCACCAUGUUAACUAGGAUGGUCUCGAUCUCCUGACCUCGUGAUCCGCCUGCCUUGGCCUCCCAAAGUGCUGGGAUUAUAGGCAUGAGCCACCGUGCCCAACCUUUUUUUUUUUUUUUUGAGACAGAGUCUCACUGUCAGCCAGGCUGGAGUGCAGUGGCAUGACCUUGGCUCAUUGCAACCUCUACCUCCUAGGUUCAAGCAAUUCUCCUGGCUCAGCCUCCCAUGUAGGUGGGACUGGAAGCAUGUGCCACCAUGCCCGGCCAAGUUUUGUAUUUUUAGUAGAGACGGAGUUUUGCCAUGUUGGCCAGGCUGAUCUUGGACUCCUGACCUCAGGUGAUAUGCCUGCCUCAGCCUCCCAGAGUGGUGGGAAUACAGGUGUGAGCCACUGCUGCCAGUCUGAAGUAUAUUUUAAAGCUGUGAUGAGUUAUAAAUGACAUUCAGUAAGCUAUGCAUAUUUAAGCUGUAGCAUGUGAUAAAUCUUGAGUUUCAUAUAAUCCCAUGAAACCAUUAACAUAGUCACAAUAAUGAACUUAACACCUUUAUAUUUACUUGGAACCUUUUUAUAAAGGCUUUCUUUCUGUUCUCCAGACAACCAAUGAUUUACUUUGCUGUACAGUAGAGUACUUUCCAUUUUCUGGAAUGUUAGAUGAGUGAUGUAAUAAAGUGUUUCCUCUUAUAA